CUCUUAGAAACUUUAGCAGCGGAGUAGAUGAGCCUGGGGUGAAGUCGGUGAAGGAGUAGACACACUGGGGUGAAGUGGGCAGGAGAAUAGAUACGCUUGGGGGUGAAGUUUGGUUGGGGUGAAGUUUAGGAGAGGCGUUGCUUAGGCCCUUACCUUGGGAUAGGGUUUGGGUGAGUUGGGAGCUGGUUGAAGACCUCGAGCUCAGAUGACAGAAAGUUAGGACUUGGGAUUCGGCGAUGGGAAGGGGCACCCGGAGCUCGGUAGCGCGGCGGGCAAGGCAGGCGCCAUGACCCUGAUUGAAGGGGUGGGUGAUGAGGUGACCGUCCUUUUCUCGGUGCUUGCCUGCCUUCUGGUGCUGGCCCUUGCCUGGGUCUCAACGCACACCGCUGAGGGCGGGGACCCACUGCCCCAGCCGUCAGGGACCCCAACGCCAUCCCAGCCCAGCGCAGCCAUGGCAGCUACCGACAGCAUGAGAGGGGAGGCCCCAGGGGCAGAGACCCCCAGCCUGAGACACAGAGGUCAAGCUGCACAGCCAGAGCCCAGCACGGGGUUCACAGCAACACCGCCAGCCCCGGACUCCCCGCAGGAGCCCCUCGUGCUACGGCUGAAAUUCCUCAAUGAUUCAGAGCAGGUGGCCAGGGCCUGGCCCCACGACACCAUUGGCUCCUUGAAAAGGACCCAGUUUCCCGGCCGGGAACAGCAGGUGCGACUCAUCUACCAAGGGCAGCUGCUAGGCGACGACACCCAGACCCUGGGCAGCCUUCACCUCCCUCCCAACUGCGUUCUCCACUGCCACGUGUCCACGAGAGUCGGUCCCCCAAAUCCCCCCUGCCCGCCGGGGUCCGAGCCCGGCCCCUCCGGGCUGGAAAUCGGCAGCCUGCUGCUGCCCCUGCUGCUCCUGCUGUUGCUGCUGCUCUGGUACUGCCAGAUCCAGUACCGGCCCUUCUUUCCCCUGACCGCCACUCUGGGCCUGGCCGGCUUCACCCUGCUCCUCAGUCUCCUGGCCUUUGCCAUGUACCGCCCGUAGUGCCUCCGCGGGCGCUUGGCAGCGUCGCCGGCCCCUCCGGACCUUGCUCCCCGCGCCGCGGCGGGAGCUGCUGCCUGCCCAGGCCCGCCUCUCCGGCCUGCCUCUUCCCGCCGCCCUGGAGCCCAGCCCUGCGCCGCAGAGGACUCCCGGGACUGGCGGAGGCCCCGCCCUGCGACCGCCGGGGCUCGGGGCCACCUCCCGGGGCUGCUGACCCUCAGCCCGCACUGGGAGUGGGCUCCUCGGGGUCGGGCAUCUGCUGUCGCUGCCUCGGCCCCGGGCAGAGCCGGGCCGCCCCGGGGGCCCGUCUUAGUGUUCUGCCGGAGGACCCAGCCGCCUCCAAUCCCUGACAGCUCCUUGGGCUGAGUUGGGGACGCCAGGUCGGUGGGAGGCUGGUGAAGGGGAGCGGGGAGGGGCAGAGGAGUUCCCCGGAACCCGUGCAGAUUAAAGUAACUGUGAAGUUUUCA